AGUUUGCUCAGCCCCCAGAGAUUCCAGGCGGCUAUUUCUGCCUUGCUCUGACCAGAUCCGGCUUCAGACUGUGAUGCAUUAUGCUCUGAGUGGAGUUUCUCUAGCCUCCUUUUCCUCAUUUCUCUUGAAUAGCUGGGGAAUGUCCGUGCCCCCCUCUCUGAGCUGUUGCUUAAAAUCAUGUAAGGCCUCAGCACAUAGUAGGUGGUCAGUCCACAGUGGCUCUUCCACCCCUCAUUCACUUCUGUCAGUAGGCGGUGGAUGCUUGUCCUCCUGGCAUGCGAUUGAGCCUAGUGCCCCUUCAACAGCGUCAGAAGACCUGGGUUGGAGUCCACUUGGGCCCCUAACCCCAUACAGGACCCCCAGCAACUCAUGUCACCUCUCUGGAUUAUAUAGUUACUUCCUCUCUGAGUUCCUCAGUUUCCUUAUCUGUAACAUGGGGGUACUCUUCCUGCCCUACACAGUUGUUUGUGUGGUCAAAUAAGGUAGACUGCUGAGGGCUUCAUGCUGGAGGCUGGAUCCUGUUCCACUGCUACAGAGCCCGGAAACAGAUUUUUCAAUCCAUCUCUGCUCUUGCUCUUCUUCCUCUCUGGUUCUCGUUGGUGCAUUGUAGGAAAUCUGGGUGCAGUUUCUCUAUGAUAACUGAUCAUUACAUGCACCUGUGCUGCACGUGUGUCCAUGCACCUGUUUCUAUCCACAGACCUCCUACUUUCAGUUUUGAUAAAACAUAACUCAGGCUUACCAUAUUUGUUUGUACUUCUUUUAUUCACUUCAGGAGACACUGGGCCUUGGUUUUCCAAAUAGGGUUUUUGACCUGGGAUUUCCUUUGCCAUGCAAAGUAGGAUAGAAAGUUGAGAAAUCUUCCCAGAGAAGCAAAGUGUUGGGUUUUCCUGGGAGGUGCAUGGUAGGACACACAUGGGAUUAGCUUGGAAGUCCUGAAAGGGCUUUGUCUCACCCAAACGAUAAAAUAUAUGCAUGAGUUGUAGUUGCUGUUCCCAAAAUUACAUUCACUGGUCCUGUGCUCUGAUAUCUACACCCAUUCAUUUACUUGAGACCCCUUGUGACAGGCUGUCCCCACCUUUAACAAGCCAGAACAUUUGGACACAGAAUGCUUCCAUCAGACGGAUUGGAAGGCUGGGGCGGGGUGGGAAGAAAUGGGUUUCCUGGUGACUUGUUCUGGGCAGGAACAGAACCUCUCAAGGGUUUGUUUCCUUUUCCUUGCAAGAAAAUGCAAACCACUGGUCUCUGCAUAUCCCUCCAGACAUUCAUGGGAGAAACCAGGCUAAUGUUUAUAGAAGCCUAUUGGGAGUGGCUGCCUUCAGGAUGGAGAGAAAGCUCAUUACCUCGAGCUGCUAAAAUUUAAUCCAAAGAAAAUAUACUAUUCCCUUAGAAAAUGGGUUGGGUACAUGUGAACUGUGUUAACUUUAAAAUCAACAAAUCAGUUAUCAAAAUACUAAUUUUCUAAGCAGUAUGCGACCAGGGAAAUGAACACAUUGUGUAAUUUGAUGUGUGUCUGUAAGUCUUAGAACCCGCAUCUAUGUUUAUCAACAAAGGGCUUCACCUUCUCUAAUGAAGUUUUGUUAAAUGUUUGGUUUGGUAUUUUUAAUUUUACCAUCCAAGAUCUGUUAAUGUAGUGUUUUUGUUCAAUUUCAAGGUAAAGUUUAUUAUUGUUUGGUGCUUACAAAAUAACAAAUGCUCAUUGUAAGAAUUUUAGAAAAGAUGGGAAAUAAAAAAAAACCUAUAAAAAUAACAGUGGUUGAACAGAAAAGGGCAUGAGGAAACUUUCUGGGGCAAUGGGAACAUUCUAGUUCUUUAUAGGGUCUUCGGUUUCUACACAGGCAUACAUAAUUGUUGAAACAUCAGCCAGUGCACCCUUAAGAUUUGUGAACUUCAUUGUACGUACAUUUUACAUUAAAAUCUGUGAACAGUUUUUGAAUUGGGUUAAUGAUAUGUAUGAUGAAGUAUUUGGAAGAAGUGUACAGAUGUCUGCAAUUUACUCUGAAGUGAAUCAAAAAAAUAAGAAAGCUUGAUGAUGAAUAUAUGGAUAGAUAUGUAAUAAAGCAAAUAAAGUAAAAUAUUAAUGGAGAAUCCAGAUCUUGGGUAUAUUAGUGUUCAUUAUAAAAUUCUUUCAACUUUGCUGUAUAUUUGAAAACUUACAUAAUAAAGUAUUAGGGAAGAGAGAUUACUAAUUCAGAAAAAAAUCCAUAUUUACAAUCCGAACUUACCACUAUUAGCAUCUUAGUGCACAUUAUUUUCUUUCAUUUUUGUUUUCAAGAAUGCAUAAUUUUAUACCAUUAUGAUCUUAUACAGAUUUAUUUUCAUAUUUUUUUCACUCAAUAUUAUAUCAUAGUUUUGUUAUGAAAAGUCUUCAUUAUGUAAUUUCUAAAUUGAGGUAUUAUUUAUGUACAGUAAAACUUACACUUUCUAGUUUAGAGUCCUGUGAGUUUUGACAAAUGCCUACAGUCAUGUAACCACCACCACAACCAGGAUGUAGAACAAUGAUAUCAUUUAGGAAAACUUCUCUGUGCCCCUUUGAGGUCAACCCUCCUCCUCACAUCCAGGUCUUGGCAACCACUGAUCUGUCUUCCAGAAUGUCAUUAAGAUGGAAUCAUGCAGUGGAGGAUGUACCUUCUGACUCUGGCUUCUUCCACCCACACACGAUACAUUCGAGAUUCAUCCACGUCCUUGCAUAACUGACCUGAAGUUUCAGUGUAGUCAGAGAGCUCUUCAAGUAAUAAAUCAUGGAGACCAGUCAGGAAACUUCCCUCUUCUUGGUGAAGAUCUUGGAGGAACUGGACAGCAAGCAAAAUACCGUUUCUUAUCAGGACCUGUGCAAAUCUCUCUGUGCCCGGUUCGACCUGUCGCAGCUUGCCAAACUGAGAAGUGUGCUCUUCUACACAGCUUGUCUCGAUCCCAAUUUUCCAGCCACGCUAUUCAAAGACAAGAUGAAAUGCACUGUGAAUAACCAGCAAUCAAAGAAAAUCAUGGUGGCAGCAGAUAUUGUGACGAUAUUCAACCUGAUCCAAAUGAAUGGCGGGGCUGCCAAGGAGAAGCUGCCCACGGGCCGCCAGAAGGUACGCAAGAAGGAGGCAUCCUUUGAAUCAUGUAGGUCGGACACAGAGAUCUGCAAUGCAGCUGAGUGUGAGCCCCUGAACUGUGAGCUGAGUGAGAGGUCUUUCAGCCGGGGCUACCCCAUCAGGCAGUCGUCCAAGUGCCGGAAGAUGGACUGCAAGGACUGCCCACAGUUUGUCCCUGCCUCUGAGCCUAACUUCCUGUUGGGAGUUAGCAAAGAGGUGAAAAACCGCGCCGCUUCCCUGGACAGGUUGCAGGCCCUGGCUCCGUACUCUGUGACCAGCCCUCAGCCCUGUGAGAUGCAGAGGACCUACUUCCCCAUGAACAUCGAAAACGAGUCCAUUUCAGACCAGGACUCCCUGCCCAUCAAUCAGAGCAUCAAGGAGACCUUCAUUUCCAAUGAGGAGCCAUUUGUGGUCCAGUCCUGUGUCCAGAAAAGGAAUAUCUUCAAAGAGGAUUUUCACAAUUUGAUGGCAGUGUCCCCCAGUUUGGUUGGCCCCAUCAGCAAAGCAGAGAAUGAGCACAGGGAACCCCAGAGUCGAAAGGAACCCCACAAGCCACCCUUCUUCAACCACAGCUUUGAAAUGCCCUAUAACAGCCAGUACCUGAAUCCAGUGUAUUCCCCGGUUCCUGACAAAAGGCGAGCAAAGCACGAAAGCUUAGAUGACCUUCAAGCCUCUACAUAUUUUGGGCCCACUCCCGUGAUGGGAACCCAAGAAGCCAGGCGCUGUCUAGGGAAGCCCAACAAGCAGACUCCCUGGCCAGCCAAAAGCUGGAGCCUAAACACAGAGGAAGUUCCUGACUUUGAACGGUCCUUUUUCAAUAGAAAUCCCUCCGAGGAGAAGCUACACUAUCCAAAUGCCAGUAGCCAGACCCCCAAUUUCCCAGCCCCAGAAAGGCGCCCAACUUACCUUGUGCCAAAGGAUCAACAGCCAAUUCUCCCCAUUGCUUAUGCGGCAAAACAAAAUGGGCUCAAAUCUAAAGAGAUCUCAUCCCCUGUUGACCUGGAGAAGCAUGAACCAGUCAAAAAGUUUAAAGACAAGAGCAUUAACUGCACCAGUGGGCAGCUCAGCUCAGACACCAGUAGCGUGGGCACCCAGACUGAGCACGUGCUGGAGCCCAAGAAAUGCAGAGACCUGUGCACCUCUGGUCAGGGCAAGUACAGUGACAGGCACACCAUGAAGCACUCAGACGAUGACUCAGAAAUUGUCAGCGACGACAUCAGUGACAUUUUCCGAUUUCUUGAUGACAUGAGCAUCAGUGGCUCCACGGGAGUGAUACAGUCGUCCUGCUACAACAGCACAGGAUCCUUGUCUCAGCUCCAUAAGUCAGACUGCGACAGUUCCCCUGAGCACAACUUAACCAAAAUUGCCAAUGGGGUCCCCAACAGCAAGGGAGACAAGGGCAACCGGCCUGAAAACACCCACCACUCGGAAGAAGAGCUGAAGACCAGUGUGUGCAAACUGGUGCUCAGGAUUGGCGAAAUUGAACGGAAGCUGGAAUCCCUGUCGGGUGUCCGUGAUGAAAUCUCCCAGGUCUUGGGCAAACUAAAUAAAUUGGACCAGAAAAUGCAACAGCCUGAGAAGGUGAGUGUGCAGAUAGAUCUGAACUCCUUGACAAGCGAGGGUCCGUCUGAUGACAGUGCCUCUCCCCGGAUGUUCCACGCACACAGUGGCUCCCACGGACCCAAACUAGAGAACAACCCUGACUGGUGCUGCUCUGAUGCUAGCGGGAGCAACAGUGAAAGCCUGCGGGUCAAGGCCUUAAAAAAAAGCCUCUUCACCAGGCCAUCCUCUAGGUCCCUAACAGAGGAGAACAGUGCCACAGAGUCCAAAAUUGCCAGCAUCUCCAACUCGCCCAGAGACUGGCGCACCAUCACUUAUACCAACCGUGUGGGCCUCAAUGAGGAGGAGAUAAAAGACACAGGCCCAGGAGAUAAUAAAGACUGGCAUCGGAAAUCUAAAGAGGCAGACAGGCAGUACGACAUUCCCCCACAGCACCGACUGCCCAAGCAGCCCAAAGAUGGCUUCCUGGUGGAGCAGGUGUUCAGCCCUCACCCCUACCCUGCCUCCCUCAAGGCCCACAUGAAGAGCAACCCCCUGUACACAGACAUGCGGCUGACCGAGUUGGCCGAGGUGAAGCGGGGCCAACCUUCUUGGACCAUUGAGGAGUAUGCACGGAAUGCGGGCGACAAGGGCAAGCUGACAGCCCUGGACCUGCAGACGCAAGAAUCUUUAAACCCAAAUAAUUUAGAGUACUGGAUGGAAGACAUUUAUACUCCAGGAUACGAUUCAUUACUAAAACGUAAAGAAGCCGAAUUCAGACGAGCCAAGGUCUGCAAGAUAGCUGCUCUGAUCGCUGCUGCGGCAUGCACCGUCAUCCUCGUUAUUGUCGUGCCCAUCUGCACAAUGAAAUCAUGAGCUAAGAAUGCAACCUUACGUACAGCUUAUGACUACCAAUGUCGUCGUCUGUAUCUUAGAAUCUUGCAGCAGUGAGGCAACAAUUUGUUGAAAUGGAGAUGAAAUCAUGGAGGCAUUUCUACAAAUGUUGAAUGAAGGUGGUUUUCAGAAAGUAUACAUUCUAGUGAGAAAUCUACCUACCUAUUAGCUUUGACUCAAUUACACUCUGACGCAUUUUUAGAAGUGCAAUAUCUUUUCCUACCAAAAGAACAUCAUGGACUAUCAAUAAAUACAAAUUGAAUAUUCCAAGCCAAAAAAGGAAGAUUAAUUGGGUUCUUUCCAUUUUGAUGAUGUUUCAUGGUGGGGAAUAAGUUAUACAGAAGAUAUUUAAUACACGCCUCUUUAGAAGAAACUAAGGGAAAUAGCAACAUAAGAAGAAAAGAGGUGGCUUCUCUUUUCCAUAAUGUUCUUAGACCAUUGCUGGUGAAGUAACAGGGUGUGUGUCCCUAAAGGGUAUUACUUCUCUGUCGACUUUUAUCAAGGGCUACUGACGUUUCAUUCUUGCCCUUUUGUCAUCAACACGACAGAGUGUCUGCAUCACUGCAGAUCUUCAUGGAAACAUUCUGGACCUUCUUCCUUGCACUUGGAGUGAGAAGGAGCUGGACUACCAAGUCAGGCGUGGAAUGAAGUAUGCUCAGACUGCAUGAUGGGCCAAGGUAUUCAGGCCAGGAGACCUCGUCCUCAAUCCAAAGUGUAGGGGAGCUGCCUGCUAACGAUGUAAGGUCAGUAUUUGAAAAUCAUGGCCACUCCAAAGGAUCUCCUGUUCUUGCUUUGGUGUGUGGCUCCAUUCCUUGAUUUUCUAUCUCCUGGUGGUACCAGAUGCUCUGCCUCUCAUACAUGAGUUGAAGAGUUUGGAACUUGUCCUUGUGCCUUGAAGAGUAGAGACAAUGGCUAAACGUUGACAUUCUAUCUGUAAACCAUGGUUUUCACGCACCACUAAUAUCUGCCAUUUUCAAUGGCUUUAAAAAGAUUUUGAAAGCUUGCUCAAUAAUGUUCAAUAAUAUAAUAAUAAUAAAGGCACUGAGGUCUUCUCAGUUACCCCAACACCUACUCCAGAGUUUUGAAUACUUGUCAGCAGUGCAAAAAAUAUUAUCUGUUUAACCACUUAUCUAUAUGUCUAUCUAUCUAUCUAUAUGUCUAUCUAUCUAUCUAAAUACUUGAUUUUUAUUUAUUGUCUUCUCUGUUAAAUAACUUGAGAGCAAGGUUUCUUUCGUGUAAAAGAAGCUGUUGUAAUUUCAUCCAAAUUUGAUCUGUUUCCACCUGCUGAAUGGUGCUCUGACAAUAAUGGAACAGAAAGAAUCCUUAUCAGCAUCUGAUUCCAAUGUCUUGUUACAGGUCAAAGAAAAAAGGAUUGACAGAAACUAGCUACCUUAUAUAUAUUUUUUGAUAAUAAGGUGGGAUAUAAAUAGAUUUUGGUAGCAAGUGUAAUCACUCCGUAUGAUAUAAUAAAUUUCUAAAAGAUUUGAGAGCAUCUCAAUUUUUAAAGCAAUAGGAGUCUAGCAUCCAUUCUGAAAAAUCGCAAAUAAUGCUUAGCUUGCUGUGUCUGAUUCUGUUGUUCACCAUUAAGGGGUAGACAGUUAAUUUUAUUAUGUUAACAAGUGAGGGAUGAAUGUUUUCAUCUGUGGUGAACCUUUAUUUUUAGAAGUCUUCAUGUUAUCUAUUUGUAUUAUCAUGUUUAUGUAUGGAUUUUCAAUUUCAGUAACCGAAAACUUAAGCCUUAGUAUGAAAAACUGAGGAUUUAUAAUUGAAAAUGAAAAAAAUAUGUUACUCUCUAUCAUCAGAAUUAUAGUCUUUGGUGCUCUGUUUUCAAUGGGGCAUAUUACAUAAGGUUGUUUCUUUCACCCCAAAGAGACUACUAGGUUACCACUCUGGGCAUUGCCUUUCCACCUAACCCCUCAACCAGUAAGACUCUACACCAUAUUGUAGCCCCACUAUUCUCCUCUUUAUCACAGAUGAAGUGCCAGAGCAUCAGAGAUAGGUAGCUCCCAACCUCUUGCUCUGGAUUUGCAGAAGAGGGGGAGAUGUACUUACCCAGGAUAAGAAAAAUCUAGUCAAAUCCACCCCAAAUCUUCCAUUUAACAGGUAGGACCAUCGAGGCUGGACCAAACCACUUUUUCCACUGCCCUUGGUGAAUCUAUUCCUAGUGGACCCCAUUUGGGCAUGUGCCUAGCUACCUUGGGAAGGCAUGACUAUAAGUCACACCUCAGGCUUGGAAAUGAAAGGAUUCUAUAGAAUAUUCUAUACUUUCCAUAGCUGGAGAGGUAGUCAGAAAUUCAGUCUUGCUCUGAGUCCACAGUAGCUUUAAAAUUCAACUCAACAUUGUUGUCACGUAACGGAAACAUCUAGACCUGGUAAUAAUCCAGGAAAUUGCAAAAUGGAGGCCAAAAGUAAGGUGGGUUUCUCUGGAAAGGGGUCAUCCUCAGUCUGAUAAUACCAAGUCUGACGCUGAGGUUAUGAAUCAUUACCAUGGCUUGGAGCUAUUGGAUGCUUGGGGUCUUGGGAUAGAUAGAAGGUGAGGUUCACAGUUGGAGCUUUUCUUGCCAUUGACCCCAAGCUCACCCCAGCCUUCCUUCCCUGACCCUGAGACUCACCCUAUCUAUCUCCCCUAUUCCCUCAGUUUGCAGAAUGAGCAAGAUAGAGUCUGGCUAGGAGGGAAACAUCUAUCCAUCUCUCUAAUCUUUGCCCAUCACCUCCUGUUGCAAUGAGUUCCCGCAGGUGACAUACGGACUGGCCUCUCUACUGUACUGGGUGCCAUCUCCCACCAUACUCUGGCAUUUUUAUGUAAAGGAUAAUUUCUUGUACCUGAGUCUAAAAUUACAACGUUAUCAAAAUUCACUUCGUUUUUCCUGCAUUUUAAAAGUAAUAAAAUAUUAUUUGAGAUUAUUUUGAAAUUAAAUAUCCUUAACCAAUGAUUAAAUUCAUAAUCAUUUCAUCUUCUUUCAUAAUCAUUUCAUCUUCUAAUCUGAAUUUGUUUUGAACACAGCCUUGCAGAAAAGCAAAAAAUAUUUCCCCGCUCAAAUUUUGCCGACAUUUUAUACCAGUAUCCCCUUCAUUACAGUAAACUAAAUCAUAACUUACAUCAUCCAUUACUAGCUGAUCAUAAAUUGUUAGUAUUUUAAGGUAUGCAACUAUGUGAUUGACAUCUGUAAGGCUAGUUUAAUAGACGUGCUAAAUAUCACUGUUCUGAAUAUCUGUGCCAUAGUUCUGAUACCCUUAUUGGAAUCAAGGCAGUGCUGUUUCUGUUUACAAGUUAUCAAGAUAAGAGCAGUGGCAUCACAUUUGUUGUUGUUGUUUUUUUUUUUGAAAUAGAAAAAAACAGAAGAAGCUCUGCCAACAAUAAAAGAUUUUGUUAAGUGGUAUAAAAAUUUGUGAAUGUUGAAAUUCAACAUGCUUCAUAUUAUAACCAACCUGCAAGAAUAUUGUGGUCAAUUGUGUGAAUACCAAAUCAGUAUAUACUGUAUACUGUACUAUGAAAAUUUGUAUUUAAAGGCAAAGAUACAAGUAAUUGUUGGUAUAAUUGGGGAAAAGGGUAUUCAAUAUUUAUUAAGUAACAAUGAGAAAUGCAACAAACUUCCUUAUUUAUGCCUUAUGAAUAAAAGAGUGUGGAAUGUAAGGUGAAAUUUUAUGUGCAAGAUCCUGAAGGAAUGGGUAUUCUUGAAGGCAGGGACUGUCUUUUCUAUGUUUGUUCUGUACAGCUCUCAGCACACUCUUGGUGCUUGAUAAAUGUUAUGUUAUAUAAUACCAAUAACUAAGCACAUUUUUAGAUCUUUUUUCAAAUGGCUUGUGUAAAAUUUGGUUAAUGUACAAUGGUUGGUUUGAAGCUAUCAUGUAAAAUUGGCCUCUCCAAAUAUAAUCAGAAAUAAACCGAAAAAAAUAUAAAA